AGCGCAGAAACAACUGUCUUCUAGAAAAGCAACUUGGUCCAGCAACCCCUUGAAGAUUGAUGGUAGAGGCUAUGCUGUAGUUUUUCCGAAACCUGUUUUUUUGAAAACAACCAAUUUGAGGUUAUGCACAGAAAUGGUGAGUUUGCCCUGAGGCAAUAAGGCUUACUUUUGAAGUGCUUACCUAACUUUAACUUAAUACAUUAUAAUUUAAAGAUAGUUCAUUGAUCUUUGUGGAAAACAUGCAGCAUUAAUGCAGCUUUCCUCUAGGGGGAAAAGUAUAAGUUGCCAAAUCCUUAUUUGUAAUCUUUCUAAGUGUAGAUAGUAUUGAUUGAAUUUUUAUUGUGGCAUACGUAAUCUUUAGUCGGAAUGUAUUGAUAAAUAAAACGUGAAAAGAGAUGUGCUUUUGGAGCUACAUUUGGUAGGGGUGGUUUUCUGAAUUACAGAACAUCUGUAUAAUUUCACUGGAAUGAAUGCAUGUGUCGUUUAAAUAUUCUUUCUUAAAGAGAAUGCCUUUCAUUCCCCACCCCCACCUUCCUGAGGCAUGAAUUAGAGUUAUUGUAUGUAGUAAAUCUGGCUCAUUUGGAAUGAAAUAUGCUUACAGUAUUUUUCUUAGUACUGUAUAGUAUUUAUUCUUAGAGUCUUGGUUCAUGUCAUGCCUAUACUGUGUUUUCAUUUAUUAGUCCUUUGGAACAUGCAAUAAAGGAGAUUUUACUGAAUACUUAUUAUUUUCCAGCCAUUUUGGUGAAAAGAAUAUUUUGUAGCUCUUGCAAUAAAUCAUACUCUGGGUUUUGCUUUGAAAGAGCUGAAUUACUUCUUGGCACAGCUUGUCUGAAAUAUGUAAAGCUAAGUGCAAGUGUUAGUUUGAUUAUAGGGGGCAGUCUGUCUGGAAAUUGGUAAAACCCACACAUUUUAUAUGUGCUUAUAUGUAGUUCUAUUAAGACCUAUGUUAAACUCUGGUGGGAUAAUUCCGUGGCACUUUCACAUAAUUUAAAUUAUGCCAUGUAAGAGUCACUAAACCCUUAUAUACUUCAGUAUGAAUCCUGUACAUUGCCCAAGACCUUGUUAAGAGAAUGUAAAUUAAAUAUAAAUUGGAGUAUCAGUGUAAAAGUGACAUUCUAAAUGUUCCUCACUCUGCGAGGCUUAUUUUUUAGGGACUUUGCUAUAAUUCUGAAAGACUUAGUUUUACAGUACAUCUGAAAGUAGGAGUUUUCAGAAGUAUGGCUCUUGGGAUAAAUUUAGAUUCUUAAUUGUGAAGCUCUGUUACCACUUGUUAGAAGGCAGGUCAGCUCACCUGCUUGGGGAGGUAAAUAUAUGAAUGCACUCUCGAGUAAUUUAAUGGAGCCCUACCUCAAUGUACAGAAUGACAGUAUCACAGAUCAAGAAUGGAGUACGAGUGAUUUUCGGCUAUGGUGGGGGUAGGUAGGUCACUUGUCCCCUGUUGUCUCUUACUAUUUGUAAAGUGAAGACUAUGAUUAGUCUUUUUGAUCGGGAUGGUUUGAGAUGAAUAAAGAAUAGGCAGGCAAUUUGGAUACUUUAGGCUUUUCAAGAACAUUAGUAACAUUUUUUCUUAGAUAUUUCUCCUAAUACAAUGAGUGUUGUGAAAUAACAUGGCAGUUAUUGUUGAGAGAAAAGCCUUCCCAGUUAUGUAUUGAGUCCUUAGGCGUUUUGACCUUCCCUCCACUCUUACAGAACUUGGUGGAAGGGGCCACUAUGUUUUCUACCUCCUUCCGUGCCUUUCACAAAGCCACAUCCUGCACCGUCUACCCUUCUCUGUGGAUAUUUUUCCGCUUGGCAAUUUCCUUUCCUGAGGCACCCACUUGGGACAUCUGAAUCUCCAUCUCCAUGUUGAUGGCCCGUUUGUGCUUGGACGUGUUCUUCCACUUGAGACUGAGGGUUCAUGUAAUCAAAGAAGUUUCUUUGUUGUGUGUAUCUUUACAGAACACAACAGGAAUUGAAAAUGAAUCAGAACACUACUGAGCCUGUGGCGGCCACCGAGACCCUGGCUGAGGUACCCGAACAUGUGCUGCGAGGACUUCCGGAGGAAGUGAGGCUUUUCCCUUCUGCUGUUGACAAGACCCGGAUUGGUGUCUGGGCCACUAAACCAAUUUUAAAAGGCAAAAAAUUUGGGCCAUUUGUUGGUGAUAAGAAAAAAAGAUCUCAGGUUAAGAAUAAUGUAUACAUGUGGGAGGUGUAUUACCCAAAUUUGGGAUGGAUGUGCAUUGAUGCCACUGAUCCAGAGAAGGGAAACUGGCUGCGAUAUGUGAAUUGGGCUUGCUCAGGAGAAGAGCAAAAUUUAUUCCCACUGGAAAUCAACAGAGCCAUUUACUAUAAAACUUUAAAGCCAAUCGCGCCGGGCGAGGAGCUCCUGGUCUGGUACAAUGGGGAAGACAACCCUGAGAUAGCAGCUGCGAUUGAGGAAGAGCGAGCCAGCGCCCGGAGCAAGCGGAGCUCCCCCAAGAGCCGGAAAGGGAAGAAAAAAUCCCAGGAAAAUAAAAACAAAGGAAACAAAAUCCAAGACAUACAACUGAAGACAAGUGAGCCAGAUUUCACCUCUGCAAAUAUGAGAGAUUCUGCAGAAGGUCCUAAAGAAGACGAAGAGAAGCCUUCAGCCUCAGCACUUGAGCAGCCGGCCACCCUCCAGGAGGUGGCCAGUCAGGAGGUGCCUCCAGAACUAGCAACCCCUGCCCCUGCCUGGGAGCCACAGCCAGAACCAGACGAGCGAUUAGAAGCGGCAGCUUGUGAGGUGAAUGAUUUGGGGGAAGAGGAGGAGGAGGAAGAGGAGGAGGAUGAAGAAGAAGAAGAAGAUGAUGAUGAUGAUGAGUUGGAAGACGAGGGGGAAGAAGAAGCCAGCAUGCCAAAUGAAAAUUCUGUGAAAGAGCCAGAAAUACGGUGUGAUGAGAAGCCAGAAGAUUUAUUAGAGGAACCAAAAACAACUUCAGAAGAAACUCUUGAAGACUGCUCAGAGGUAACACCUGCCAUGCAAAUCCCCAGAACUAAAGAAGAGGCCAAUGGUGAUGUAUUUGAAACGUUUAUGUUUCCGUGUCAACAUUGUGAAAGGAAGUUUACAACCAAACAGGGGCUUGAGCGUCACAUGCAUAUCCAUAUAUCCACCGUCAAUCAUGCUUUCAAAUGCAAGUACUGUGGGAAAGCCUUUGGCACACAGAUUAACCGGCGGCGACAUGAGCGGCGCCAUGAAGCAGGGUUAAAGCGGAAACCCAGCCAAACACUACAGCCGUCAGAGGAUCUGGCUGAUGGCAAAGCAUCUGGAGAAAACGUUGCUUCAAAAGAUGAUUCGAGUCCUCCCAGUCUUGGGCCAGACUGUCUGAUCAUGAAUUCAGAGAAGGCUUCCCAAGACACAAUAAAUUCUUCUGUCGUAGAAGAGAAUGGGGAAGUUAAAGAACUUCAUCCGUGCAAAUAUUGUAAAAAGGUUUUUGGAACUCAUACUAAUAUGAGACGGCAUCAGCGUAGAGUUCACGAACGUCAUCUGAUUCCCAAAGGUGUACGGCGAAAAGGAGGCCUUGAAGAGCCCCAGCCUCCAGCAGAACAGGCCCAGGCCACCCAGAACGUGUAUGUACCAAGCACAGAGCCGGAGGAGGAAGGGGAAGCAGAUGAUGUGUACAUCAUGGACAUUUCUAGCAAUAUCUCUGAAAACUUAAAUUACUAUAUUGAUGGUAAAAUUCAAACUAAUAACAACACUAGUAACUGUGAUGUGAUUGAGAUGGAGUCUGCUUCGGCAGAUUUGUAUGGUAUAAAUUGUCUGCUCACUCCAGUUACAGUGGAAAUUACUCAAAAUAUAAAGACCACACAGGUCCCUGUAACAGAAGAUCUUCCUAAAGAGCCUUUGGGCAGCACAAAUAGUGAGGCCAAGAAGCGGAGAACUGCGAGCCCACCUGCACUGCCCAAAAUUAAGGCCGAAACAGACUCUGACCCCAUGGUCCCCUCUUGCUCUUUAAGUCUUCCUCUUAGCAUAUCAACAACAGAGGCAGUGUCUUUCCACAAAGAGAAAAGUGUUUAUUUGUCAUCAAAGCUCAAACAACUUCUUCAAACCCAAGAUAAACUAACUCCUGCAGGGAUUUCAGCAACUGAAAUAGCUAAAUUAGGUCCUGUUUGUGUGUCUGCUCCUGCAUCAAUGUUGCCUGUGACCUCAAGUAGGUUUAAGAGGCGGACCAGCUCUCCUCCCAGUUCUCCACAGCACAGUCCUGCCCUUCGAGACUUUGGAAAGCCAAGUGAUGGGAAAGCAGCAUGGACCGAUGCCGGGCUGACUUCCAAAAAAUCCAAAUUAGAAAGUCACAGCGACUCACCAGCAUGGAGUUUGUCUGGGAGAGAUGAGAGAGAAACUGUGAGCCCUCCAUGCUUUGAUGAAUAUAAAAUGUCUAAAGAGUGGACAGCUAGUUCUGCUUUUAGCAGUGUGUGCAACCAGCAGCCACUGGAUUUAUCCAGCGGUGUCAAACAGAAGGCUGAGGGUACAGGCAAGACUCCAGUCCAGUGGGAAUCUGUCUUAGAUCUCAGUGUGCAUAAAAAGCAUUGUAGUGACUCUGAAGGCAAGGAAUUCAAAGAAAGUCAUUCAGUGCAGCCUACGUGUAGUGCUGUAAAGAAAAGGAAACCAACCACCUGCAUGCUGCAGAAGGUUCUUCUCAAUGAAUAUAAUGGCAUCGAUUUACCUGUAGAAAACCCUGCAGAUGGGACCAGGAGCCCAAGUCCUUGUAAAUCCCUAGAAGCUCAGCCAGAUCCUGACCUCGGUCCGGGCUCUGGUUUCCCUGCCCCUACUGUUGAGUCCACACCUGAUGUUUGUCCUUCAUCACCUGCCCUGCAGACACCCUCCCUUUCAUCCGGUCAGCUGCCUCCUCUCUUGAUCCCCACAGAUCCCUCUUCCCCUCCACCCUGUCCCCCGGUAUUAACUGUUGCCACUCCGCCCCCUCCCCUCCUUCCUACCGUACCUCUUCCAGCCCCCUCUUCCAGUGCAUCUCCACACCCAUGCCCCUCUCCACUCUCAAAUGCCACCGCACAGUCCCCACUUCCAAUUCUGUCCCCAACAGUGUCCCCCUCUCCCUCUCCCAUUCCUCCCGUGGAGCCCCUGAUGUCUGCCGCCUCACCCGGGCCUCCAACACUUUCUUCUUCCUCCUCUUCAUCUUCCUCCUCCUCUUCGUUUUCUUCUUCAUCUUCCUCCUCUUCUCCUUCUCCACCUCCUCUCUCCGCAAUAUCAUCUGUUGUUUCCUCUGGUGAUAAUCUGGAGGCUUCUCUCCCCAUGAUAUCUUUCAAACAGGAGGAAUUAGAGAAUGAAGGUCUGAAACCCAGGGAAGAGCCCCAGUCUGCUGCUGAACAGGAUGUUGUUGUUCAGGAAACAUUCAACAAAAACUUUGUUUGCAACGUCUGUGAAUCACCUUUUCUUUCCAUUAAAGAUCUAACCAAACAUUUAUCUAUUCAUGCUGAAGAAUGGCCCUUCAAAUGUGAAUUUUGUGUGCAGCUUUUUAAGGAUAAAACGGACUUGUCAGAACAUCGCUUUUUGCUUCAUGGAGUUGGGAAUAUCUUUGUGUGUUCUGUUUGUAAAAAAGAAUUUGCUUUUUUGUGCAAUUUGCAGCAGCACCAGCGAGAUCUCCACCCAGAUAAGGUGUGCACACAUCACGAGUUUGAAAGCGGGACUCUGAGGCCCCAGAACUUUACAGAUCCCAGCAAGGCCCAUGUAGAGCAUAUGCAGAGCUUGCCAGAAGAUCCUUUAGAAACUUCUAAAGAAGAAGAGGAGUUAAAUGAUUCCUCUGAAGAGCUUUACACGACUAUAAAAAUAAUGGCUUCUGGAAUAAAGACAAAAGAUCCAGAUGUUCGAUUGGGCCUCAAUCAGCAUUACCCAAGCUUUAAACCACCUCCAUUUCAGUACCAUCACCGUAACCCCAUGGGGAUUGGUGUGACAGCCACAAAUUUCACUACACACAAUAUUCCACAGACUUUCACUACCGCCAUUCGCUGCACAAAGUGUGGAAAAGGUGUCGACAAUAUGCCGGAGUUGCACAAACAUAUCCUGGCUUGUGCUUCUGCAAGUGACAAGAAGAGGUACACGCCUAAGAAAAACCCAGUACCAUUAAAACAAACUGUGCAACCCAAAAAUGGCGUGGUGGUUUUAGAUAACUCUGGGAAAAAUGCCUUCCGACGAAUGGGACAGCCCAAAAGGCUUAACUUUAGUGUUGAGCUCAGCAAAAUGUCGUCGAAUAAGCUCAAAUUAAAUGCAUUGAAGAAAAAAAAUCAGCUAGUACAGAAAGCAAUUCUUCAGAAAAACAAAUCUGCAAAGCAGAAGGCCGACUUGAAAAAUGCUUGUGAGUCAUCCUCUCACAUCUGCCCUUACUGUAAUCGAGAGUUCACUUACAUUGGAAGCCUGAAUAAACACGCCGCCUUCAGCUGUCCCAAAAAACCCCUUUCUCCUCCCAAAAAAAAAGUUUCUCAUUCAUCUAAGAAAGGUGGACACUCAUCACCUGCAAGUAGUGACAAAAACAGUAACAGCAACCACCGCAGACGGACAGCGGAUGCGGAGAUUAAAAUGCAAAGCAUGCAGACUCCGUUGGGCAAGACCAGAGCCCGCAGCUCAGGCCCCACCCAAGUCCCACUUCCCUCCUCAUCCUUCAGGUCCAAGCAGAACGUCAAGUUUGCAGCUUCGGUGAAAUCCAAAAAACCAAGCUCCUCCUCUUUAAGGAACUCCAGCCCGAUAAGAAUGGCCAAAAUAACUCAUGUUGAGGGGAAAAAACCUAAAGCUGUGGCCAAGAAUCAUUCUGCUCAGCUUUCCAGCAAAACAUCACGGAGCCUGCACGUGAGGGUACAGAAAAGCAAAGCUGUUUUACAAAGCAAAUCCACCUUGGCGAGUAAGAAAAGAACAGACCGGUUCAAUAUAAAAUCUAGAGAGCGGAGUGGGGGGCCAGUCACCCGGAGCCUUCAGCUGGCAGCUGCUGCUGACUUGAGUGAGAACAAGAGAGAGGACGGCAGCGCCAAGCAGGAGCUGAAGGACUUCAGCUACAGCCUCCGCUUGGCGUCCCGAUGCUCUCCACCAGCGGCCCCGUACAUCACCAGGCAGUAUAGGAAGGUCAAAGCUCCAGCUGCAGCCCAGUUCCAGGGACCAUUCUUCAAAGAGUAGACACUCUGGCUGCUCCCUGACAGCACCUGAAGUGACCUGGAAUCAGUGAAGCCAAAGGGACUGGCAGUCUGCCCUGCAGGGAGUACCGACCUAUCCCAGUUGUGUGAGGCUGCGAGAGAAAGGGAGUGCAUGUGCGCGCGUGCAUGUGUGCGUGCGUGUGUGUUCACGUGUUCUCGUGCGGGCGCGUGAGUGGUCUUCAAACGAGGGUCCCGAUCCCCGGGGCGGCAGGAAGGGGGCCGACUCCACGCUGUCCUUUGGGAUGAUACUUGGAUGCAGCUCUUGGGACCGUGUUCUGCAGCCCAGCCUUCCUGUUGGGGUGGGGCCUCUCCUACUAUGCAAUUUUUCAAGAGCUCCUUGACCCUGCUUUUUGCUUCUUGAGUUGUCUUUUGCCAUUAUGGGGACUUUGGUUUGACCCAGGGGUCAGCCUUAGGAAGGCCUUCAGGAGGAGGCCGAGUUCCCCUUCAGUACCACCCCUCUCUCCCCACCUUCCCUCUCCCGGCAACAUCUCUGGGAAUCAACAGCAUAUUGACACGUUGGAGCCGAGCCUGAACAUGCCCCUCGGCCCCAGCACAUGGAAAACCCCCUUCCUUGCCUAAGGUGUCUGAGUUUCUGGCUCUUGAGGCAUUUCCAGACUUGAAAUUCUCAUCAGUCCAUUGCUCUUGAGUCUUUGCAGAGAACCUCAGAUCAGGUGCACCUGGGAGAAAGACUUUGUCCCCACUUACAGAUCUAUCUCCUCCCUUGGGAAGGGCAGGGAAUGGGGACGGUGUAUGGAGGGGAGGGAUCUCCUGCGCCCUUCAUUGCCACACUUGGUGGGACCAUGAACAUCUUUAGUGUCUGAGCUUCUCAAAUUAGCUGCAAUAGGAAAAAAACAAAUUGGGAAAUGAAAAAAAAAUGGGAAGAUUAAAAAGCACAGGGGGAAGAAGAAGAGAUUUCGGAGGCCAUCCUGCCAGGGGCGGACGGGGCUGACUCCUGCUCUCUGGAGGACGGUCAGUCCAUGUCUCGGAGAAACGGGUGAGCUGAGCUUGGCGUUUGGACCCAGUUCAGUGAGGUUCUUGGGUUUUGUGCCUUUGGGGCAGACCCCAGGCAAGGAUGUCUGAGACCACUUGGGCGCUGUUUUCUCAGCUCCAAUUUCAAGAGUGAGCUAUCAAACCCAGAGCGGAAGGAGGGAGCUCUGAUGAGCACGGUUUGUCACACGAUAAAGGGAUUUUUUUUUUCAGGGCUACUACGGUUGAUCUUGCAACUCUGUAAAUAUGUAUGUAGACACUUUUAAAAGCACGUAUUUAUGUCCCUGACUGUAAAUGCUCCAUUUUUAAAGUUUUAUAACUUGUGUUAUUUAAUGAGUCAGUCAAUCGGCUGCAGUAUGGGAUCUGAUAAGGAUCUAGGAGAAGGGUCUCAUGCGGACCCUCACAUGGGCAGAAAAAUGGUGGUCAUUGGCCGACAUCACAGUUUUCCUGUUUCCCACCCAGCUAAAAACCGUUGUUUGCUUUAAAUUUUCAUAAACUGGAAUCCUUUCACCCGCUCCUACAGCUAACCCUCACAAGCAUGAAGUGCUGUGGCUGUUCCUUAUCCUAAUGAUGCGCUUUUGUCCCGUAAAUGUUAACACUCAUGAAGCAUACCCCGGCCUCUCAGUUCUUGAGGGCCUCCCCACCGCAGCAGCAAGGAAAGCUCACGAACCCCAAACCUGGCAAGUCACCUGCAGCCCAUGGUGAGCUCUGGGAAGUGUGGUUGAGGCCUUGGGGUCACUCCUUUUUUGCAUGUGCAAAUGUGCUGGUCACCCUUCAACGCUCCCAGACGGUCAGGAAAACUGUUCCAAUCAUGAAAAGGGGGGAUGAUUUUGUAAAAGUGGCAUUUCCUGGUCAGUGGUGGUCUUCAAGACGACAGCUCUGUAUCUGCCAUGUGAAGAGAAUUAACAAUAAAAGUGUGAAGAGCGAUUGUGAGGAACAA